AUGACAGGGCCUUUCCGAACAAAGAUAUACCGGCAGGCCAAAGCAGCACGCCGAAAAGCAGAGCAAACAGGGCGGGGUCCUCACCAGGAAGGUGCUAGGGAAAGAAAGGAGCAGGUGCACCCGAGGCUCUGCAACACCCACUCCGGAACGCCUCCCCCGGCCCAUCGGCUCCCACAGCACCAGAGACGGCGGAAAUCCUGCAGCUCACAGCCCAACUGCAACUCUUCAGAGUCGCGUCGCUCCUCAUCCGCCCUUCUACACCCCAAACUCUGGACACCGAGAGUUCCACAGAGGGAACGCGGGGAAGAACUAUGGCCACCAAGGCCUGUUUCUCUAAGAACUCGACCCAGUGCCCCUAGCACCCAAACCAGAGUCCCCGCUCCGCUUCCUCCGCCCGCAAGGGGGCACGGGAAGCCCGGGGCAGGAAGACCCGGGAACCUACAGAGGAGGCGUGGGCCCGUGGCCAGACCCAACAGGGCCGAGUGUCCCGGAGCCGUUACUCUCCCGCCUCUGGGGCGCGCCGCCCUAGGUUGCCAAGGGCUGGGGACGCGCAGGCAUUACCUCUACAAGAAGCAGCCUCUCCUGUCAAAGGCAGAGCGACAGUCAGCCCCCACGACCCGCCGCCGGCAGCGGUCGGCCCUCGGAGACCGCAGCAGAGAGGCCCACACGUUUCCUGGCUGCCUCGGCCCCAGUGGCCGCCUUUUCGACCUCAGCUACGCAGCGCCAACCGCCGCAGCCACCGCCAUCUUAGGAUCUCAUUGUGGUGGGAGAAGAGGGGCGGGGGUACUGCAGAGGGGGCAACGCGCGGCGGGACAUGCGCCGUCUCCUCGGCAACGGCCGCGCGGGGGCGAGAACUCGCCCGGGCGGGAGCCGCAAUGCGAGCUAGACUGGAGUCAUGUGACCCGCCGGAGUCUGUGGUGUCGCUUCUGGCUCUUUAAGCCGAAAAGAGAUUACACCAACGAAUCCGCCCCCACCCGCCCAGGAACUAUGUAUCCCAGAAUGCCAACUAGACCUCGCGUUCUAAACGCCUGCCGGCCACAGGUGGAGGACUACAAAUCCCAGCAUGCCGUGCGCUUCCGGCGCUGAUCGCGGAGCGUGGGGCCCUAGGCCUAUGCGGAAGUGCAUUGAUCCCUCAGCCCGUGGAGAAAGAGCGGAGGCGCUGUGCGGUUUUCCGUGGGGGUGUCAGCUCCGGCCCGUGCCGGAAGAAGGAGCCAAGACCGGGAUCGCUUUUUUGCCCCUUCCUCACCCCACAUUCGGUCACGAAGAGGUGGAAACAAAAGGACACUUACAAUGUAGUCCAACCUCCUGAUUUUACAUAUGAGGGGAUUGUUCCACGGAAGUUAAACAAUUUGCCAGACGUCAUUAUGUAUCUACUGAGUGAGAGAAUCAUAAAUAUUGUUGAUAGUUAACGCCACUUUUGGUUAAUGUCCCUUUUCCUUAAAAGAGCCAGAUGAUUUUAAUCCAAACUUAAUUUCAGUAAAUUUUCUCUGAACUAUCUUUUUAUUUAUACUCUCCUGUUACAGCUCUAUUAAGAUUAAUAAAUUGGCAGGUCCUCCCUUUAAAAAACAAAAAUCAAUAAAGUCACAAGGCCUUCAAUGUGCCUGACUGGAAAGGUAAAACACCUGUCAGUUUUAGUUGAGUGCAAGGGCAUUCUUCUAGUUUUACGCAGUUUAUAAUUAUGGAAUAACUUUUUAAGCAAAAUAAAGGUAAAAAGAAGAAUUGCAUUCUGGGUUUCAACAACAAAAACAAAUUGUUCCCAAAAUAGUAGGUCUGCAUCUCAGUACGCAAUUCACAUAAAGCUCUUCUAUCCCACUGCAAUCUGCCACCGUAGGUUCAGUCGUGAGUGCAUUGAUCGUUGGUCAGACACUUUUUCCUCAUAUUCUGUGUGUGUAUCGCUAACUACUGCGGUAGCAAAAAUAUAGUCCCUGCCCUUGAAGAGCUCAUAUUUUAGUGAAGGAUGCGGAAGUGGAGUGUGAUGUAAAUAAAGUUUGUGUUGUAAGAAAAAGUGCUGUGGGAGCUCAGAACACAGCAGCUAAACGCUCAGGUGUUUAUUGUAGUCCAGAAUGCCCUAUCCUAAUUCCACCACUCCAAGAUCCUGGACAAGCGACGUGCCUUUCUGAGCCUUAAUUGCCCCAUCUAUGAAAUGAGGGGGAAGGAAUGAUACUGCCUACCUUGAAAGGAUUUUUUAAAAAAUGUUCUCAGAGUUUGUUUUAUGCCAGGCACACUGUAAAGCACUUCGGCUGUUGUGAUUUUCUUGAUCCUCACAGUUACCCUGAAGAGGCUGGUUCUGAAUCUGACCCGUUUUGGCAAUGAAAGAUUAUAUAAAUCAAACUUGUAGCAGCUGCAAGUGGUAGAGCCUAAAUUUAAACGGAGGUCUAUGUGAUUCCUUUAAGAUUUUUUUUAAUUAAAUACAACGCAUAUAAAAACACUAGUAUAUGUUGAGGCCCGAAAUAUUAGCUAUCAUCAUUAUUUUGCUUUAUACAUAUGUAUUAUUAUUAAACGUAUGUAGAAGCUGUUAUCAUUAAAACAAUUCUAAUAAAUUCAAAAGCGUGAAAUUAUAAUACGUACUAGUCAUUAUGUUUUCUGAAUUUAUGAAGCUCCAGAAUGUCAAUACUAUUGUUUAUUAGGAGGUAGGAGGAAUUUGAGAAAUAUUUACAUUGAAAUGUAGAAGCUGUUAUCAUUAAAACAAUUCUAAUAAAUUCAAAAGCAUGAAAUUAUAAUA